GUCUCAAGCUCUGGAGCUAGCGCAGGGGCGGUGCCUCCAAGUGACUGCCGUGCAGAUCCAGGGGAGUUGGAAGGUCACAGGAGUUCAGCCUCAGGUCAGGCCCGACGGGGCAUGUAGUUAGAAGUUAAUGACAGUUGAAACGUGGGUCAGCUGGUUCCUAGGCCCGUGCACACGUCUGCAAGGGACGUUGAUCCUCACUCUCCAAUGCGUGUCAGUGGCAUAUGGGGGCUGGGGUGGGGGAGGGGCGGUAUCUUAGGGCUUGGAUAUAGGAGGAAAAGAAACAGAACUUUUCAAGGACUGGAUGUGCAGGGUGGUGUCAGGGGUUGCCGAGAAGGGCCCUACUGUUUUAGUGACUCGUUUCUUUUGGUUGUUGCCCCUUCCUUCCAAGUUGCUCUUAAUAAGUUGAGUCCGAAUCUUCAGGCAGGAGUAAAGAUGUAGGAGGAAUGGGAUUGGUUGUUGAAGUCUUUGGAAUCAGGUAGCCAUCCAGGUGGAAGGCAUUGCCCCUGAGGCCUGUCAUCCAAGGCUUGUCAUCAGUUGCUUUGUGUAAUAGUCGCAGCAUGGCAAGUAGGUUAAAAGUCGCCUGCAGGUAAUGUGGGUGAAACUGAAGUUUCCUAAUACAGGACCAGGAUAUUAUAGUGUUAGAGUUAGGAGGAUACCUCAUGCUCACCUGGUUAAACCCCAGGUUUCAUAGGUGAAAGCAACAGGCCUCAAGGGUGAAGUCACUCCUGAAAUGGCCCAGAUAAGUGAAUAGCAGAGGUGGGAUUGGAGGGUUCAUGAUCUUGUGAAUGUCAAACAUGUGGUUGCCUUUUUAGGCACUUGCAUUUUUGUUUACAUCAAAUAUAGUGUUUUUAUAUUUUAAAACAGAAAACAAACGUUUGCAAUAUUUAGAAGUUGCUCACCUGUUAAACAGGAAUGAAAACUCUGCCUGUCUCAUUGCAGGAAUGAAAACUCUGCCUGUCUCAUUGCAGGGUUGUUAGGGGGUUCAAAUCCAAUCUGUCAGAUAUGUGUGAAAAUUUGAUAGCUGUAAAUAACUCUACAAUGCACAGGACAGUGACCCCAUACCUCUCCCGGGGAAGAAUUAUCCAGUCCCAAAUUGUAAUAUUGCCAAGGUCAAGAAACCCUACUCUAAAUAAAUGGAGAAUAUAGGUAUUAUGAAGAAAUUUCCUGUCUAAAUACAUAUAUAUUUGCUUUGGAUGCAGUCCGUCCCUCUCCAGUUAGUGGGACUGUAAAACAUGCUAUUUGGAAUACUUACAAAUUAGUAGGGCUGGCCUUUACAUAAUCCAGAACACAGCAGAUACUGCAAGUGGCUAAGCUGCCAUAUUUACUUUUUUUCUGUAUACAGAUGUUAUAUCUUGAUGGAUUACUCACUCAACAAACUCUGAAUGCUUGCUGUGUACUAGGACCAUUGGGUUUAACAAGAUGAUCAAGAAGUUCACAGUCUAGAACAGGCAGAAUUAAUUUCUUAGGGUAACUUUAAAAGGUACCUUAGUUUGAAAAUUGAUACAUUUUCAGAAAAAGUCUUUCUUUUAAUUUUUAUUUUUUAGAGAUGAGGCCUUGCUAUGUUGCCCAGGUUGGUCUUGGAACUCCUGGGCUCAAGCAGUCCUCCUGCCUCAGCCCUCAGCCUCCCAAAGUGCUGGGAUUACAGGGAUGAGCCACCACACCCAGCCAGGCAAAAUUCUUUUAUCUUCUCUGCUAUUCCAUUUUUCUUACCAGCCACAUCAAGGCUUUGGCCAAGUUUUGUUGAUUCAACUGCUCAGACGUGUCUAGCAUCUGGCUUAUUUCCUCCCAUUUUCUUUCCUUUAUCUUUGCUACUUUGGGUACUCAGCACCCCUCACUUAGAAUUGCAGUGACCUCUUAACUAGUUUUUGGCCUACCAGCUCUCUGCUCCUGUCUAUCCUACACCUUCCAGUGCAGUCAAACAUCUGAGAAGCAGUGAUCUUAUCACUACCUUUUCAGUGGCCUAUUGAUUGCAGAAAUAAUAAUAAUCAUCACUGUAAUAGCUAACAUUUAUUGCAUGAUUUCUUAUAAUUCAGGUGCUAAGUGUUUUGGAAGUAUUGAUUUACUCAAUCCUUGCAUCAACCCUAUGAUAAGGUACUAUGAUGAUCACCUUUUUACCUAUAUAUAAAUGAAUGCAUAGAAAGGUUAAGUUGGUUUCUCAAGAUUCCAGCUAGGAUCCAAACCCAGCUGUCUGCCUCCAGUCCUGUGUCUUCAACAUGCUCCUGCAUUGCCUCUCCAAACAGAAGGCAAAUGCUGCCUGGUGGGUACACUGAACUAAUUUGGUCUCAACUCACAUUUCCAUCAUUCUCUCCCAUUACCAUAGACCUGACAUCUUCUCCUCUAGCGAGCCCAGACCGCUGUGCCAUCUUCCCUGUAUACAGACGAGGCAGUUGAGGUCCAGGGAAAGUCAGUGGCAUAUACAAAGCACACGGCUAAGAAGUGGUGAAUAAAACUGGGAUUUAGAUCCAAGUCCAUCUGCCCAUGAAGCCCCUACUCUUUCCCCAAGCCACACACACUCUUUUUCUAAUAAAGCUUCCAGCAUGUGGGAUGGACCGUCUUAGGAGGGUGAGUCCUCAUUAUUGGAAGUACAGUACUGUGUUGGAGAAAAAACUCAAACUGUUUUUUUCAUUAUCUCAACAUCACCAACAACACAGAAGCACAGAAGACUCCUGUGACCAAAUGUCUGAGGAUUUCUCUCCAAACACCAAAAGACUGGACUUUAUGAGUAUAAAGUCUUUGGUGUUCUGGAGGACUGCUCACCAACUCUACUGGCAGACAUCUAUAUGGACUCAGAUUACAGAAAACAAUGGGACCAGUAUGUUAAAGAACUCUAUGAACAAGAAUGCAACGGAGAGACUGUGGUCUACUGGGAAGUGAAGUACCCUUUUCCCAUGUCCAACAGAGACUAUGUCUACCUUCGGCAGCGGCGAGACCUGGACAUGGAAGGGAGGAAGAUCCAUGUGAUCCUGGCCCGGAGCACCUCCAUGCCUCAGCUUGGCGAGAGGUCUGGGGUGAUCCGGGUGAAGCAAUACAAGCAGAGCCUGGCGAUCGAGAGUGACGGCAAGAAGGGGAGCAAAGUUUUCAUGUAUUACUUCGAUAACCCGGGUGGCCAAAUUCCGUCCUGGCUCAUUAACUGGGCCGCCAAGAAUCAGAGCAGAACCAAGCGGGAAGCUCAGAAUCAGAGAGACCUCAUCAAGUUUUUGGCAAACCCAAACAUUCUGCAAUAGAUUGAGUGGAAGGAAGAGGAAGGACAUAAAGAUAAAGACAUGAGAAAAGAAGCUGAGUCUUUGUUGAAACACUGAAAUGGGUGCAGACUCUUCAAAAUACUCUUCAGUGGCUUUGUUUCCAAAUGAAAACCAGAAAAAUGAUGCUGGAAUUUCAUAGAGGCAGCGGCGGAUGGAAGAGGGCUCCUCCUGUCUAUAACCAUGGGAAUAUUGUUUUUGAUUGUAGACCAACUAACUGCAAAGAGAGAAGACACAUAAAUAAGACAAGCCCUGGAAAGCACAUGUGGUGUGACGGUGUCCUGCCAAAGCUGAGAAGACACAAAUAAAAAGUAAUUAUUUACUCUUUGUAAGAGAGUGUUCUAAACCCAAGACACUGAUUCAUAGAUGCUAUCAUGGCCCUGUAAACACAUUAAAAAUCAAAUACAGGUUAUAUUACAUGUACCCAGUUCAUCUUACAAUGGUAAAGUCCAGAAAUUGUCAACAGUCUAAAAAAAUUCUAACUACUUGUCAUAUUAAUGAUGUGUAAUAAGGUAUAAUAUUGAUAAUAUUUUAUAUUAUAAUAAUGUUAUAUUAUCUUAUUUCUUCUAGUCUUGAUCUUGUUUGUUUUCAGGUCUUAGCCAUGAGGGCAUUUAAAAUGUUUUCUGAUUAUGUUUAAGGAUGAUUGCACUGCAUGAAAUCCUUCAGAGGCCUCACACUUCUUUUAGGAUAAGAUUCAAAUGGCUUAUGAAGCACUAGGAAGUCUUUUUGAUCUGCCCCCCUCCCCAUCUACCUCUCCAGACUCAUCCUGUGCCACUGUCCCACAGGCAUCCUUCCUGCUGCCAGAACAACUUUAUGCAGUUCCACGAAUAAACCGUGGUGUUUCAUGCGGCA